ACACACCCCAGUACACCAGCAGAGGAAACUUAUAACCUCGGGAGGCAGGUCCUUCCCCUCAGUGCGGUCACAUACUUCCAGAAGAGCGGACCAGGGCUGCUGCCAGCACCUGCCACUCAGAGCGCCUCUGUCGCUGGGACCCUUCAGAACUCUCUUUGCUCACAAGUUACCAAAAAAAAAAGAGCCAACAUGUUGGUAUUGCUGGCUGGUAUCUUUGUGGUCCACAUCGCUACUGUUAUUAUGCUAUUUGUUAGCACCAUUGCCAAUGUCUGGUUGGUUUCCAAUACGGUAGAUGCAUCAGUAGGUCUUUGGAAAAACUGUACCAACAUUAGCUGCAGUGACAGCCUGUCAUAUGCCAGUGAAGAUGCCCUCAAGACAGUGCAGGCCUUCAUGAUUCUCUCUAUCAUCUUCUGUGUCAUUGCCCUCCUGGUCUUCGUGUUCCAGCUCUUCACCAUGGAGAAGGGAAACCGGUUCUUCCUCUCAGGGGCCACCACACUGGUGUGCUGGCUGUGCAUUCUUGUGGGGGUGUCCAUCUACACUAGUCAUUAUGCGAAUCGUGAUGGAACGCAGUAUCACCACGGCUAUUCCUACAUCCUGGGCUGGAUCUGCUUCUGCUUCAGCUUCAUCAUCGGCGUUCUCUAUCUGGUCCUGAGAAAGAAAUAAGGCCGGACGAGUUCAUGGGGAUCUGGGGGGUGGGGAGGAGGAAGCCGUUGAAUCUGGGAGGGAAGUGGAGGUUGCUGUACAGGAAAAACCGAGAUAGGGGAGGGGGGAGGGGGAAGCAAAGGGGGGAGGUCAAAUCCCAAACCAUUACUGAGGGGAUUCUCUACUGCCAAGCCCCUGCCCUGGGGAGAAAGUAGUUGGCUAGUACUUUGAUGCUCCCUUGAUGGGGUCCAGAGAGCCUCCCUGCAGCCACCAGACUUGGCCUCCAGCUGUUCUUAGUGACACACACUGUCUGGGGCCCCAUCAGCUGCCACAACACCAGCCCCACUUCUGGGUCAUGCACUGAGGUCCACAGACCUACUGCACUGAGUUAAAAUAGCGGUACAAGUUCUGGCAAGAGCAGAUACUGUCUUUGUGCUGAAUACGCUAAGCCUGGAAGCCAUCCUGCCCUUCUGACCCAAAGCAAAACAUCACAUUCCAGUCUGAAGUGCCUACUGGGGGGCUUUGGCCUGUGAGCCAUUGUCCCUCUUUGGAACAGAUAUUUAGCUCUGUGGAAUUCAGUGACAAAAUGGGAGGAGGAAAGAGAGUUUGUAAGGUCAUGCUGGUGGGUUAGCUAAACCAAGAAGGAGACCUUUUCACAAUGGAAAACCUGGGGGAUGGUCAGAGCCCAGUCGAGACCUCACACACGGCUGUCCCUCAUGGAGACCUCAUGCCAUGGUCUUUGCUAGGCCUCUUGCUGAAAGCCAAGGCAGCUCUUCUGGAGUUUCUCUAAAGUCACUAGUGAACAAUUCGGUGGUAAAAGUACCACACAAACUAUGGGAUCCAAGGGGCAGUCUUGCAACAGUGCCAUGUUAGGGUUAUGUUUUUAGGAUUCCCCUCAAUGCAGUCAGUGUUUCUUUUAAGUAUACAACAGGAGAGAGAUGGACAUGGCUCAUUGUAGCACAAUCCUAUUACUCUUCCUCUAACAUUUUUGAGGAAGUUUUGUCUAAUUAUCAAUAUUGAGGAUCAGGGCUCCUAGGCUCAGUGGUAGCUCUGGCUUAGACACCACCUGGAGUGAUCACCUCUUGGGGACCCUGCCUAUCCCACUUCACAGGUGAGGCAUGGCAAUUCUGGAAGCUGAUUAAAACACACAUAAACCAAAACCAAACAACAGGCCCUUGGGUGAAAGGUGCUAUAUAAUUGUGAAGUAUUAAGCCUACCGUAUUUCAGCCAUGAUAAGAACAGAGUGCCUGCAUUCCCAGGAAAAUACGAAAAUCCCAUGAGAUAAAUAAAAAUAUAGGUGAUGGGCAGAUCUUUUCUUUAAAAUAAAAAAGCAAAAACUCUUGUGGUACCUAGUCAGAUGGUAGACGAGCUGUCUGCUGCCGCAGGAGCACCUCUAUACAGGACUUAGAAGUAGUAUGUUAUUCCUGGUUAAGCAGGCAUUGCUUUGCCCUGGAGCAGCUAUUUUAAGCCAUCUCAGAUUCUGUCUAAAGGGGUUUUUUGGGAAGACGUUUUCUUUAUCGCCCUGAGAAGAUCUACCCCAGGGAGAAUCUGAGACAUCUUGCCUACUUUUCUUUAUUAGCUUUCUCCUCAUCCAUUUCUUUUAUACCUUUCCUUUUUGGGGAGUUGUUAUGCCAUGAUUUUUGGUAUUUAUGUAAAAGGAUUAUUACUAAUUCUAUUUCUCUAUGUUUAUUCUAGUUAAGGAAAUGUUGAGGGCAAGCCACCAAAUUACCUAGGCUGAGGUUAGAGAGAUUGGCCAGCAAAAACUGUGGGAAGAUGAACUUUGUCAUUAUGAUUUCAUUAUCACAUGAUUAUAGAAGGCUGUCUUAGUGCAAAAAACAUACUUACAUUUCAGACAUAUCCAAAGGGAAUACUCACAUUUUGUUAAGAAGUUGAACUAUGACUGGAGUAAACCAUGUAUUCCCUUAUCUUUUACUUUUUUUCUGUGACAUUUAUGUCUCAUGUAAUUUGCAUUACUCUGGUGGAUUGUUCUAGUACUGUAUUGGGCUUCUUCGUUAAUAGAUUAUUUCAUAUACUAUAAUUGUAAAUAUUUUGAUACAAAUGUUUAUAACUCUAGGGAUAUAAAAACAGAUUCUGAUUCCCUUCAUUGUGUGAAUGUUUUUUUCUAAAAAAAAUGUGGAGAAAUAUGGAUAAUUAUGACAUUUAUCCCUCAUUAAGCUGCCUAUCAGUUUGAUUUGGACAACUUGACAUUUAUUUGAGACAUUAAGCUACUUUCUGGUAAUAUAUUAGGCAUUUCUGCAAUAGCUCUUUCAGGUAACUGAAUAUUAUUAAGCAUAGUUUUAUCUUGCUUUGAUUAAACCUCUUAGGCAAAAAAUGGAACUUCAUAAGCUAAUACAUUAGAAAGGGGUUAUGAUUAUAAAUCAGAAAUGCUUGUGACAUUAAGAAAUGAGGCACUUGUGAAAUUUCUUUGAAAUAGCCAGCUCCUCUAAUGUGUCUUCAAAAUAUAAAGUGAUUCACAAAGGCAUGCAUCACACCUAUUUGUAGCAGCCCAUUCAUUACAUAAACCAGGGCAUACCUGUGUGGGCUCUGUGAGUGAAGGGAGGCUUCACUACUUUCUGUGAGCAGUAAGGACUGGUAUCUUUCUGUGAGCAAUAAGGACUGGAUAAAGACUGCAUAUCCUUGUGUCGUGUCAGCACCAAUACAAUAAGGAGGGUUUUAAUGUGAAGCAGGCAAUCUUCCAGCCCCUUCUGGUCUUGGAUGAAAUAGUUGCACAGAGUAUUGCACCAAAAAUACACAAUGGAGGCUGAAAAGUUCAACAUAUUUUAAGUCAAUUAAUCAAAUUGCAUUGAUUCUUGAUGCUUUCUUAGAGGCCUACAUGAUUUCUUAGAUUGCUCUGAUAAACUAUCAUAAGGGGUCCACCUCCCCUCAUUUAGCUCCCCCAGGGAUUUCUUUUCCCCCAUGUCAUACACCCAGUCCUAAAUCAACCCCCAAGGCUAUCCUUCCAUCCCUUCUGCAGAGGGAACUUUUGUCAGACUCUGCAACAAACUCCUAGCUCUAUCCAGAGUGUCCUCUGCUGCUAAGAUUGGUAUCUUUCUCCUCAAAAGCCUGGAUGGUGAAUGGGGGUGCAUUAGUCAGAAUUCUCCAGAGAAACAGAAAAAAUAAGAUUCGCGUGUGUGUGCAAACAUAUAUAUAAAUAAAUAAAAAUAUAUUUAUUUUAAGGAAUUGACUCACAUGAUUUUGAAGGCAGGCAAGCCCAAAGUCUGCAAGGGGUGGGCCAGCAGAGAGCUGGUGCUACAGUGCGGGUCUGAAAGUUGCCAGAGUCCCUUUUAUAGAGAAGCUUAAAAAAUAUUUGUUGAAUUAAAUGUCUUAGGUAGAGACAAAUUGAAUUAAAGUGGUUAAGUAAAUACUCUUAGGUGAAAUUUGUGCAAAUUAUGAGUAUAAAGAGGGUGAGCUACAGAACUCUCCAUGACCACUCAAGAAUGGGACCCAAAGGCAAAUGAUAACUUAUUCAUUCAUCAAGGGAUAAACUUGAGUUAUCAAAUGGUUAAUAGAUAAAGAUCCCACUCUGCCUUGGAUUUAGCCAUCGCAGUCCCUGUGUAAAACCCCACCGGCUUUCAGGCAUGGAAAAAAAUUUCACAAAGGCCUUGAAAGAAGGCAUAUGAAGACCAAAAGGAUAUUGAGCAGGGUUCCAUACUUGAAUAAAGGAAGAAACUCCCUUCAAUGUUUACUAAGAAAUAGUUAGAAUAUAGCAUAUCCUGUAUAGAUGAAAUGUCCUAGCGAAAAUGUUUAAAUGUAUUUAAAGAAGAGCUAGAUUUUGUGGGGGGAGAGAAGGGAAUAGGAUAGGCUGGUGGGAGGAAGAAUGAAAAGAAGAAAACUUGUUGGAAAUUUUGGAGUAGAUUGUGAGGAGGGGUGACUCACUUUAAAGAUGUAUCAUUUGGAGGUAGACACGAUUUUCAGAGCACAAAACAGAUAAGGAAAGAUGUAUGCUGAUUGUGUGGAGCCCAAGGGAAGGCGGGGUUUUGGAGUCUUACGUGGCUUUGUUUCUGAAAGGGAGACAUGUGAAGCCUACUCCUGAGGCGGGAGGCUGGGGACAUGACCAUCAAGACCUAUAAUUGAUAAACAACUAGGGGCUGGGUGCUGCACCUACAUGCUGGGGAAAUAGAAAAUGAAGCAGACAUGUGUCCCAUCUUCUUCCAGCUUUCAGUCUAGCUUGGAAAUAAAUCUCAUACCUAGAGAAAAUGGAGGAUCUGUGGGAUGUAGAUGAGGUGGGAGCAUGAAUGCCUAGGGAGGGAAGAAGAAAGAUUUUCAGUUCUUCAGCUUUUCCUCAUGACCCUAUCUCAUGCCAUGAGCAAUUGUCUGGCAUCUCCUGUGGGUUGGACCACUGCUGCAUUUCUUACUUGCCAACAUCACUUUGUCCCAAAUGCCAUUCCUUUGUUCCAGGGCCUCCUUGUCUUCCAUCUGGGGAACUGGAGGUGAGAAGCAUUAUAAUAGCCUCUCUGCCUUUAUCUACAAUCUCUCCAACCUGUGCUUUAUGCUGAUGUCAGGAUGGGCGUUGAUGGAUGCUUCUAUCACUGUCGGGGCAGGGAGGGCCAGAACACUAGCAUAAGAUGUCAAUAUGUCUAUCCAUAUGUCAGGUCCAUACUCAACUCAAGCUUCUGGUUAACUGCUGAUCUAUUGGCAACUCCAGUUCCCAAUAAGUUCCUCAUCUCCUUCUGAGACCACCUCAGUGUGGACUUAAUCGUCCACAUCACUGUCAGCAUUUUGGUUAAAACCAUUCAACAAGUCUCCAGGAAGCUCCAAACUUUCCUUCAUCUUCCUGUCUUCUUCUGAGCCCUCCAAACUCUUCCAACCUCUACCCGUUACCCAGUUCCAAAGGUGCUUCCACACUUUCAAGUAUCUUUAUAGCAAUGCCCCACUCCUGGUACCAAAUUCCUGUAUUAGUCUGUUUUCACACUGCUAUGAAGACAUACUUGAGACUCGGUAAUUUAUAUAGAAAAGAGGUUUAAUUGACAAAAAAGCUAACAAAGUGAGCCCUGAUUCAAAAAUGACUGUCUACACUUGGCACAUGAGGGACUUUAUGAUAUUAAGAGAUUAAUUAAACAACAGUGGAUGGGGAGGAAGAACAGACUUUUGAGCUCUUCCCAAUAUAGGAAUGUGUUAGUUCUAAAAAUUUUCUUAAGUUGUUUGCUUGGAACUCAGAGUAUAUUUUUCCAUACGAAAAAUUCAGAACUAUUUUAUUUAUGAUAUGGGCUAAAAAGACUUCUGUAAUCUAGCUUGGAAACUUAAUAAUCAUUAAACUUAUUUUCAAUGAGA